GCAGAGCGUUCCAGAUCCCUGGGCGUCAGCGAGCCGUGAGAUGCGUGGUCCACCAUCGGUGACCUCACCGCCUCGGUUCGCCCUCAGCCGCCCCGGUGAGCUGCGCUCCUGCGGGUCCCUCUCUGCAGCGCGCCCUUCCGGCGCAGGAAGAAGGGCCGGGAAGGCCUGGGACGUGAGGGCGCUGCUGGGGCCGUAGCGCGCGCUCCUCCAGGCCCGGCGUCUCCGCGUUCUGGGGAGGGGCGGAGACCCAGGCCGCGCCUUGAAGUGGGCGGUGGGGCUGCGGCUUGCCGAGCGCCCCGGGUCUGGGCCGCCACUCAGUCUCCGUUCCCGGUUGCGUGUAGUGGCGGCUCGGGCGGUGAACAGCCCGGAUUUCACAGGGGCGCCGAGCAACCCAGGUCCUCUUGUGCCAGGGUCGCCGCUCCUCGGGUGGGGACGGGCCAGCGGCCUAGCGAGCUGCCACGGGGGUCUUUUGGCCGGAGGUGGAGGGGGACUCGGCCACAGCCAGGGUCCACUGGUGGGGUGGGGGUUACAGCCAUGAGACGGAUGGGCUAGGUCCGACUCGGGUUCCCUCCGACUCUGAUGCUCCAGACUUUAUUGUGGGAGGCGGGACAGGGGAGGACUUCGCCCGCGUGUUUUGGGGAAGGGCCGCUGCUUUGGGUUGGGAGCACCCCGCCUUGGGACGAUCUUCCGCGGAUAGGAGUGUAGGCCGGGACCAAAUGUCCUCGCACGGGCACGUCUAGACGUGUUUUGGUGGGGGGGGGGGGGGAUCUGCGUGGGGCAGCGUCCGCGGGAGGUGAGGUGGCUGUGGGGACCCAGGUGGCCUCUUCCCUGGGGCCUUGCUAAUGACGGCAAAAUCCGGGUUCUGCCAAAAUAUAUUUAAAAAGGUUUAUUCCUAGUCAGUAUGAGUGACUGUGGCCCAGGUUAUUCAGCCUCAAGAGGUCCUGUGAAAGUGCCCGAGAUGGUCAGGCUUGCAGGUUAAUUUUAUACAAUUCAGGGAGACAGGAAUUUCAGGUAAAGUCAUAAAUCAGGCUGAGCAGUGUGGCUCAUGCCUGUAGUCCCAGCACUUUGGGAGGCCAGGAGUUCCAGAGCAGCCUGGGCAGCACAGCAAGACCCUGUCUCUACAUGAAAUUAGAAAAAUAAAAAAAUUAGCGGGGCGUGGUGUCCCAUGCCUGUGGCCUCAGCUACUUGGGAGGCCCAGUCAGUUGAGUCCAGGAGGUGGAGGCUGUAACCAGCUAUGUUGGCUGCACUGCACGCUAGCCUGGGUAACACAGCGAGAUCCUGCCUCCAAAAAGAAAAUCAUAAAUCAAUAAGAGAAAGAUAUACACGGGUUCCUCCCAAAAAGCUGGUAUAUCUCCAAAGGGUUUACACCUCAUGGGGGCACUUAGGGAUUCUUUAGUGGACAGUUGGUUGAGAGACUUAAGCUACUGCCUGAAGACUGGAAUCAGAAGCAUGCCAGAGUUAAGGGGAUUGCGUAGAUCAAAGUUCUUAUUAUGUAGAUGAAGCCUCUUAGUUGGCAACUCUCAGAAUAGAUGGUAAAUGUCUGUUUUCAGUUUUUUGGGUUUUUGUGUUUUUGUUUUUGUUUUUAGAGAGAGUCUUGCUCUGUCGCCCAGGCUAGAGUGCAGUGGCGUGAUCUCAGCUCACUGCAACCUCCACCUCCCAGGUUUGAGCAGUUCUCCUGCCUCAGCCUCCUGAGUAGCUGGGACUACAGGCGCCCGCCACCACGCCUGGCUAAUUUUUGUAUUUUUAGUAGAGAUGGGGUUUCACCAUGUUGCUGAGGCUGGUCUUGACUUCCUGACCUCAGGUGAUCCACCCACCUCUACCUCCCAAAGUGCUGGGAUUACAGGCGUGAGCCACCGCGCGUCAGGCUGGCUGUCUCUUCCAGACCUAAGAAAGGCUUAGAACAAAGGAGGUCUGGCUACAUUAAUGGAGAUUCGCUGCAGAUGCAAAUUUUCCCACUAAAGAUAGCUUUGCGGGGCUAUCCAUUUCAAUCUGUUGCCCCUGUGGCAGCCACUUCAAAACAUGUCAAAGAAGUAUAUUUUGGGGUAAAAUAAUUUCCUUCAGCAUCUGCUGUCAUGUGAUGCUGUACCAGAGUCAGGUUGGAAAGUGAGCCUCAUUAUAUAAGAGUAAUAAAACUCAUCUGAUGAGAUUUUAUGGUUUCUCGGGCAGGAUUCCCCAAGCCUCAUACAUAGGCAUUUGGGCAAGGGAAAAAAGGUGAAUUUAGUCCUCACCAGGUUGGUAGGGCUUCCUCGGUUAUUGGAGUGGGAGUAACAGCAACCAUUGGGCCCAGCAGUUUUUUUAAAUGUCUCUGGGGCUGUGGACUGACCAUCCAAAUAACUGAUUUUAAUCAUUUCAUUAUGGAAAAAUUGUCAGCAGAACCCCCAAGUAGAGAGACCCAUCAGUCAAGAUAUACCUCAUGACCUUGCAAGCUAAUCUAGCUUGACCCAGAUCCCCUCCUAAUCUGUGCAGAUUCAUUGAGGAAUGUCAUAGCCAUGCCUACUGGUUAAGACAUAGUCCUUUACAGUGAGAGUUGAAACCCAAGCUCUAUCACUUUCUUGGCUGUGUUGCUUUGAGAAAGGCAUUUAAAUGUUUUGUGCCUGUUUCCUCAUCUGAAAUUGGUGGGUAAUAGUCACUUCAUAGGACAGUUGUGAAGAUUGAAUGCAGAAAAAUUUGUGCCACGCCUGGAACCGUCCCUGGCAUAUAUUAAAUUCUAAAAAAGUGUUAAAUAUUAUAAUGAAUAUCAACACUUCCUUAUUCUGGAAGCACCGACAGGAUAUGCUGUGUUUAGUGUUAGCAUCAUGUCAGGACAGGGUCUGUUGCGAUGCCCACACUCAGGAUCUGUUCCCAGGAACCUGCGUAAAGUUUUCUUCUCUGGAAGACUUUGGGUCCUUUUUUUUUAACAAGAAGAGGCUCUACCCUGGGACUGGGAAUUUCCAAGGCCACCUUUGAGGAUCGCAGAGCUCAUUUUAGAGCCAUUUUAGUCCCCAGCUCCUCUUCCUCCACUCCCACGUUACCCGUGAGAGGACUGUCUGCAGGGUAAGGGAGGACAGCCCAACCCCAGGUGGGGACUUCUUAUGUAUUGCCUUCCUGCAGUGCCUUCUCUGCCCUAAACCAUGGUGGGUUUCCUUUGCUAAUGUCUGACAUCUUGUGCCCUACACUGUCCCAUCUGAGGCUCAGAACCUCUCAGCCGGUUCUCAUGGGGAACGUUCCCCAGAUCUGAUGCCCUCAUUCAGGACACUUCCAUCAUUGUCCCUACAUUUCUUCUCUCAGUGCUUUAUUCAGGCUGCUGCAUUCGUGGUGCAGACCAGGUCUUGUAAAAAAUUAUUCAGUCAGCAUGUGCUGAGCCAUUGUCCUGUCCCAGGGACAGGGCUUUAUAGUCAUUGCCCUAUUCAUCUCUUCAACCAAUGUGGAAGUUAGGAAUUGGAAUCCCCAUUUCACAGACUAAGAAGUGGCGUGUUAAUCAGUUGAAAUAAUUUUUACGGCUUGGCGUGGUGGCCCAUACCUGUAAUCCCAGCACUUUGGGAGGCCAAGGCGGGCAGAUUACCUGAGGCCAGGAGUUCGAGACCAGCCUGGCCAACAUGGUGAAACCUCAUCUCUACUAAAAAUACAGAAAUUAGCCAGGCAUGGUGGCUCACGCCUGUAAUCCCAACUACUCUGGAGCCUGAAGCAAGAUAAUCGCUUGAAUCCAGGAGAUGGAGGUUGCAGUGAGCAGAGAACAUGCCACUGCACUACAGCCUGGGGGACAGUGAGACUCUGUCUCAAAAAAUAAUAAUUUUUACUUUAUGUAACAUAUCUGGGAUCAAGUGGACUGGGUUGUGGAGCAAGCUGGGAUUUUGGGGGUUUCUGUUAAGAAUUAGCUUCAUUGAGGUAUAAUUGAGACAAUAAAAUUAUCUCCCAUUUUAAGUUCUAGUUGAUGAGUUUUGAGAAAUGUAUAUAGUGAAGUCUUGAUCAUCAAAUCAACAUAUGAACAUUUUUCAUCUCCCAAAAAUGUAGGAGCUGUUUUUUUAUCUUAGGAGAAUUUUAAUGAAAUAUACGUGGAGGAGCUAAAUGUUUCAAGUUUGCCUCAUAUUCAUAUCUAAUUUAUUGGUAACUAAUUUAAACCACUUUCUUACGGCUCUCAGUUUCUGUUCCUACAGGAUAUUAACUCCCACAGAUGGCAACAGAUGGCAGGAGUGAGACCAAACAGUUUGCAGUGUUCUCCAUUCACACCCUGGAAAUGAAAGUUUUCUCUAUUUUUCCUCUCCAAAUUAUCUUGGAAGGGAUAUUCAAUUUUUUUCAAAUUUACUAUGAAAAAUAUUGAAGUAGGAACUAAAGUAGAGAGAAUAUAUAACAGAUCUCUCUGUUCCCUUGUUGCACCUUAACACUUUGCUCUUCUUAUUUCAUCCAACCCCCUCCCCACCCCAUGCUUUCUGUUUUCAGGCUAGAGCAUCUUGAAGCCAAUCCAAGACACCAUUUUAUCUGUAAAUUUACUGCAGCUACUUCUCUGAGGACUAUUUUUGUUGUUACUGUCUUGCCUUUUAACGUAACUAGAGUACCAGAAUCAUACUCAACAAAAUUAGCAAUGUAUUAAUUUCACUCAUUACCCAGUUUAUGCAGAAAUUUUCCAGGUCUCAAAAAUUUCUCCUUACAAUUCAGAUUUCACACUCAGGUUCAUUAAGAUGGGAAGCAUGAGAGAAGAAAUAUCUAGAAACCAGCUCAGUAGUGCCCCUUGUCUGUUUUACUUCUCUCGUUGUGAUCUAGGUAAAGGAAGUUUCCCUACCUUGGCAAACUUCCCAUUUGCUUGCUUAGGUGCUGAGGCUUGUUCAUUCUUUCCUUGCCAUAGCUUUUUCCUUCCCUUCCUUCCUUCUGCCUGCCAGGCUCAUCUCCUAAUUCUACUUCUACCCAUAAGGACAAAUAAUGAUCACACCACUUACCUAAUUGCCUGGCCCUAGUUCUGGUCCCAACUAUAAUCAGAAAUGUGGAUUCUGGAAUGGCAGUGAGGAGCGACGUGGACUGUAUCUCCAGUAAAACACCAUAACUGGUAAUUUAGAAAACCAAAAACAACCAUUUAAACUACACGGAAUUUGUCUUAAGACCACUCAGGAAUUUAGAGAAACAUUUAUUCAGAAAAAUCAACUGAGCCUUUCUGAGAACAGUGAGAGUCUGUAACAUUUGACACACAAACUGCUACCCUCCCCACCCCCAUUUUGGUCCACUCUGAGAGAAACUCCACUGUGGGCUGUGAAAAUCACAAGAUGGAACCCUGUCCCUCUCCAGUUCUCAGUCUAUGGUGACAGCUUUUCCCUGAGAGAGGCACGAUGCCACUAUUCUUAACUUCUCUCCCCCUGCCAGUCCUGUGUUCCUGAAGCUGGUUUCAUAUUGGCCAUCUGCAAGCUUCCCUUCUCCGUGGAGAGCAGGAAGACAGUCAUGGGACCUCAGGGAGCCAGGAGACAGGCUUUCUUGGCAUUUGGGGAUGUCACUGUGGAUUUCACCCAGAAGGAAUGGAGGCUGCUGAGCCCUGCUCAGAGGGCCCUGUACAGGGAGGUGACACUGGAGAACUACAGCCACCUGGUCUCACUAGGAAUUCUCCAUUCUAAACCAGAACUCAUCAGGCGGCUAGAGCAAGGGGAAGUGCCCUGGGGAGAAGAGAGAAGACGCCGGCCAGGCCCCUGUGCAGGAAUAUAUGCAGAACAUGUCCUGCGGCCCAAGAAUCUUGGACUUGCACAUCAGAGGCAACAGCAACUACAAUUUUCUGAUCAAAGCUUCCAGAGUGACACAGCUGAAGGUCAAGAGAAAGAAAAAAGCACUAAGCCCAUGGCAUUUUCCAGCCCACCCCUAAGACAUGCAGUAAGCUCAAGGAGGAGGAACAGUGUAGUGGAAAUAGAGUCUAGUCAAGGCCAGAGGGAAAAUCCUACAGAAAUAGACAAAGUAUUGAAAGGAAUAGAAAAUUCAAGAUGGGGAGCAUUCAAGUGUGCAGAGCGUGGGCAAGACUUCAGCCGGAAGAUGAUGGUAAUCAUACACAAAAAAGCACAUUCCAGGCAGAAACUUUUUACAUGCAGGGAGUGUCACCAGGGCUUUAGAGAUGAGUCAGCAUUGCUCUUGCACCAGAACACACACACAGGAGAGAAGUCCUAUGUGUGCAGUGUGUGUGGGCGAGGCUUCAGCCUCAAGGCCAACCUCCUCAGACACCAGAGGACACACUCAGGAGAGAAGCCUUUUCUGUGCAAGGUGUGUGGACGAGGCUAUACCAGUAAGUCAUACCUCACUGUGCAUGAGAGAACACACACAGGAGAGAAGCCUUAUGAAUGCCAGGAGUGUGGGCGAAGGUUUAACGAUAAGUCCUCAUACAACAAGCACUUGAAGGCGCAUUCAGGGGAGAAGCCUUUUGUGUGCAAGGAGUGUGGGCGAGGCUAUACUAAUAAGUCAUACUUCGUUGUGCACAAGAGAAUACACUCAGGAGAGAAGCCUUACAGAUGCCAGGAGUGUGGCCGAGGCUUUAGCAAUAAGUCACACCUUAUCACACACCAGAGGACACACUCAGGGGAGAAGCCCUUUGCGUGCAGGCAGUGUAAGCAAAGUUUUAGCGUGAAAGGAAGUCUCCUCAGACACCAGAGAACACACUCAGGGGAGAAGCCUUUUGUGUGCAAGGAUUGUGAGCGAAGCUUUAGCCAAAAGUCAACUCUUGUCUACCACCAGAGAACACACUCAGGGGAGAAACCUUUUGUUUGUAGAGAAUGUGGGCAAGGAUUUAUUCAGAAGUCAACCCUUGUGAAACAUCAGAUCACACACUCAGAGGAGAAGCCUUUUGUGUGCAAGGACUGUGGACGAGGCUUUAUCCAAAAGUCAACCUUCACUUUACACCAGAGGACACACUCAGAGGAGAAGCCUUAUGGAUGUCGGGAGUGUGGGCGAAGGUUUCGGGAUAAGUCCUCCUAUAACAAGCACCUGAGGGCACACUUGGGUGAGAAACGUUUUUUCUGCAGGGAUUGUGGGCGAGGCUUUACCUUGAAGCCAAAUCUCACCAUACAUCAGAGGACACACUCAGGAGAGAAGCCCUUCAUGUGCAAGCAGUGUGAGAAAAGUUUUAGUUUGAAGGCAAAUCUUCUUAGACAUCAGUGGACACACUCGGGGGAAAGGCCAUUUAAUUGCAAGGAUUGCGGGCGAGGCUUCAUCCUAAAAUCAACUCUCCUCUUCCACCAGAAGACACACUCAGGGGAGAAGCCUUUCAUCUGUAGUGAAUGUGGGCAAGGAUUUAUCUGGAAGUCAAAUCUUGUGAAACACCAGCUUGCACAUUCUGGCAAGCAGCCUUUUGUAUGCAAGGAGUGUGGGCGAGGCUUCAACUGGAAGGGAAAUCUCCUCACACACCAGAGGACACACUCAGGGGAGAAGCCCUUCGUGUGUAAUGUGUGUGGGCAAGGCUUCAGCUGGAAGAGAAGUCUCACCAGACACCACUGGCGGAUACACUCAAAGGAGAAGCCUUUUGUUUGCCAGGAGUGUAAGCGAGGCUAUACCAGUAAGUCAGACCUCACUGUGCAUGAAAGAAUACACACAGGAGAGAGGCCUUAUGAAUGCCAAGAGUGUGGACGAAAGUUUAGCAAUAAGUCAUACUACAGUAAGCACUUAAAGAGACACUUACGUGAGAAGCGUUUUUGUACAGGGAGUGUGGGUGAGGCUUCAUCUUGAAGUUAUAUCUCACCAUCCAUCAGAGGACACACUCAGGAGAGUAACUUUGCUUUGUUACAAGCUUUAGUUGAGGCUGCAUAACUUGUUCGUGAAGAUAUAACAGAGGCAGACAGAAUCCAGAGGGCUACAGAGAACCUGAAUUCAACCCAUGUGUCCCCAAGAGAUUCAGAGAAAAGAGGUCAAUGUUUAGGGAACAGAGAUGCCAGUUGAGGGGAGGGCAUUACCUGGGCUAUUGGGGAAAUGUGGUCUCUUUCCUACUGAGCACAUAUUCUUGUUGUAUUUGUGCCAGGCUGUGCUUUCUAAGGACUGCUCUUAGCCAGUGACUGCAGAGCAGGGAUACCAAGGCAGGCCUGUUACACUCUCCCCAACCUCCUUGGACUGCAAACAAUCUAGGACACCUCCACCAAACCUCCUCUUGCACUUUCCCUCUGGCUUCCCUCCCAGCCUUCCUUGGUUUGGAUGUUUUGUCCCCUCCUUAAUUUAUGUUGAAACUCUACAUAAACUGUUUACUGUUGAAACAGUGUAAGUAUUAGGAGGUGGGACCUUUGGGAAGUGAUUAAGUCAAGUCACGAAGAUAGAGCUUUGCGAAUGGGAUCAGGUGCCCUUAUGAAAAGGCUUGAUAGAGGGAGUUUGUCCUGUGGCCCUUCUAUUUUCUGCUCUGUGAGGACACAAUGCUCCUCCCUUCCAAAAGAUGCAGCAUGAAGGCAUCAUCUUGGAAACAGACAUGAGCCCUCAACAGACAACUGCACCUACUGAUGUUUUGAUGUUGAACUUCCCAGCCUCCAGAACUCUGGGAAAAUAAAGUCCUCUUUAUACAUUUCCUAGUCAGUGGUAUUUUAUUAUAACAGCUCAAAUAGACUAAGUAACUGCUCCCCUCAUCAUUCUCUCACAGUCAUAUCUGGAAAUAAAAUCUCUGUAUAUGCAGUCCCAUAUUGGUCUUUGCAGAGAACUCCCUCCAACACAGCUGAUACCAAGAACAGUCUGACAAAACAAGUGGUAAAAUAGGGAUCUGGGGACCACUCACCUGCCUGGCAGGAGUAAAGCAUGUUGGCUGGUGGGGCACAGGUAGGUGGUUAGCUGCAAAAUAUUUCACAGGUGAUUUCCUGAGAAAAUGCCUCAAUGAUAGAGAAUGCUGUGGCAGAUGUGAUGAUGCAGGCCUUUGAAAAUGUAGGGAAAGUGCCUACAAAGAGCAGAGUAGACUGAUUAUCGCCGAUCUGCAUUACCACCUGCAGAAGGACCUUGAGAAAUUGAAGACUUCAUUCAGCCAUUAGCAAACAGUUAAUGGUUAAGUAAACCAGGACUCCCUGGUGAGUGCUUACAAGGCCUUUAUCUUCUUGGAUAGAAGGCAGAAUUAUUGCCCAAAUAUGUGGGCUGAAGGCCUGUAGCAGAGCUCUACAGAUGUUGGAAUGCUCAGCCAAUGCAUGUCUAUUUUGUAGAGGUCAGACCCUUCGUAAGGAAAAUCUGGGAUCCUGAAAAAUGACACCGGAACAUCUCCAUGGAUGCCCAAGAUUGCCUCUGCCAUGCUCCCAGCCACAGACCAUCUGGGUGUGUAGAGAUGGCCCAUCCUUCCUUAGGAAUAGCAUUUCCACCAUUCAUUACCACAGAACCUUCACAAUUAAGGCCAGCUUAAUGAGCAUGUGCCCUACAUAGCUGCACACAACCCUUGUCCAGCACAGGGAAGAUACAUGCAAUAUGCCUAUCCUUUUGUAAAUGGUAUUUGUGAUGCUUGCCCUUCAACUUCCAUAACUUUCCUCAUACUCAUUUUGAGUUUCACUGCACAUUGUGGGUUCACCAGAAUUCUGUGCUCCUCUUCCAUAUUAAACACAUUUACAUCUGA